GCUACCCCUCAGGCGCCGGGCCAGGCGGGCGUAGAGCUGCUGAGGAAAAGCCCGCGCCCCCGCAGGCCGGUCUCACCUUGCCAGGCACCCCGCGCCACUCUCCAAGGCGGCUCUCAAGUACUUUGGGCAGCUUUUUGGCCAUAACUCGCCAAACCCAAAUUUCAUUUCCCAGUGUGUCAGGACGAGACUCCUGGGCGCGCCACUCCUUUCUCCUUUCUUGAGGAUUCUCCCAGCACUUGUGUAUUCCUCUUUUCCAUCUGUCCAUCGAUCUAUCCUGACUGGAAUCCAAAGUGCUCGAGGUCCAGGUCUUGCUCCUCUUAGGGGCUCCAGGCAAAUGCUUCUUUGGGGAGAGCGCCGCGCUGCGGGUUCGGGUGCGAGGUUUCCUCUGCCGCUGACGCCUCUGCGAGCCUCCGGUCCUCCUCUCUCCACUUGCCUCCGUCAGCGAGAGAGGGAGGGUCUGAAAACAAAAGUGUUGAUGACUGAGGACCGUCUUUAAAACCUGUUCUACACACUUUGGGAGGCUGAGGCGGGCGGAUCACGAGGUCAGGAUAUCGAGACCAUCCUGGCCAACAUGGUGACACACCGUCUCUACUAAAAAUACAAACAUUAGCUGGCUGUGGUGGCGGGCGCCUGUAAUCCCAGCUACUCAGGAGGCUGAGGCAGGAGAAUCGCUUGAACCUGGGAGGCGGAGCUUGCAGUGAGCCAAGAUCGCACCACUGCACUGCAGCCUGGCGACAGAGCCAGACUCUUAUCUCAAAACAAACAAACAAACAAACAAAAAACACCUGUUCUACAAAGCAAGGUGGUGGUUUUACAGUGAAAGUUGAAAAGUAGCUGAACUGCUGGAAUUGACCAUACACCUUCUUAAAUGUUCUUUUCCGAGCAGCGGACCCUUUUGAAACCAUGCUGAAGUCAUUAUUAAGGUAUCAAUCUGGUGGUGGCAGUGUGAGUGAAAACCACAUGAGGAAAAAAUUGUAUGAAAAUGGUGUGACUGAUUCUCUGAAGAGUAACUUUGCCCUCCUCCUAAAGCUUUCAGAAGAAUUAUUAGAUAAAUGGCUCUCCUACCCAGAGACCCAGCACGUGCCCCUCAGCCAGCAUAUGCUUGGUUUUGCUAUGAAGUCUGUUACACAGAUGGUAAUGGGUAGUACAUUUGAAGAUGAUCAGGAAGUCAUUCGCUUCCAGAAGAAUCAUGGCACAGUUUGGUCUGAGAUUGGAAAAGGCUUUCUAGAUGGGUCACUUGAUAAAAACAUGACUCGGAAAAAACAAUAUGAAGAUGCCCUCAUGCAACUGGAGUCUGUUUUAAGGAACAUCAUAAAAGAACGAAAAGGAAGGAACUUCAGUCAACAUAUUUUCAUUGACUCCUUAGUACAAGGGAACCUUAAUGACCAACAGAUCCUAGAAGACAGUAUGAUAUUUUCUCUGGCCAGUUGCAUAAUAACUGCAAAAUUGUGUACCUGGGCAAUCUGUUUUUUAACCACCUCUGAAGAAGUUCAAAAAAAAUUAUAUGAAGAGAUAAACCAAGUUUUUGGAAAUGGUCCUGUUACUCCAGAGAAAAUUGAGCAGCUCAGAUAUUGUCAGCAUGUGCUUUGUGAAACUGUUCGAACUGCCAAACUGACUCCAGUUUCUGCCCAGCUUCAAGAUAUUGAAGGAAAAAUUGACCGAUUUAUUAUUCCUAGAGAGACCCUCGUCCUUUAUGCCCUUGGUGUGGUACUUCAGGAUCCUAAUACUUGGCCAUCUCCACACAAGUUUGAUCCAGAUCGGUUUGAUGAUGAAUUAGUAAUGAAAACUUUUUCCUCACUUGGAUUCUCAGGCACACAGGAGUGUCCAGAGUUGAGGUUUGCAUAUAUGGUGACCACAGUACUUCUUAGUGUAUUGGUGAAGAGACUGCACCUACUUUCUGUGGAGGGACAGGUUAUUGAAACAAAGUAUGAACUGGUAACAUCAUCAAGGGAAGAAGCUUGGAUCACUGUCUCAAAGAGAUAUUAAAAUUUUAUACAUUUAAAAUCAUUGUUAAAUUGAUUGAGGAAAACAACCAUUUAAAAAAAAUCUAUGUUGAAUCCUUUUAUAAACCAGUAUCACUUUGUAAUAUAAACACCUAUUUGUACUUAAUUUUGUAAAUUUGGAUUUUUAUAUAUCAUAUUUUCUUAAUUCAUUGUACACAUUUGACUUACUGCACAGUAUAUUGAUCAUUUUAAUGGGAAACUUUAGCUUUCUACUUUUUAUUUUUGUUUUUUCACUUUCUAUGCCAUUAUUUUUGUAUUCUUUUUCUUAGUGUGAGCUCUAAAAUCAAUGUUCUUGAAAAAGAAAUUAUUUUGCAGAAGUUGGGGAAUCAUGUUUGUUGAAUAUGUAUAAAAUAGAAACAUAGGCUGGGCGCGGUGGCUCACACCUGUAAUCCCUACACUUUGGGAGGCUGAGGCAGGUGGAUCACCUGAGGUCCAGAGUUUGAGACCAGUCUGGCCAACAUGAUGAAACCCCAUCUCUACUAAAAAUACAAAACAUUGGCCGGGAGUGGUGGCUCAUGCCUGUAAUCCCAGCACUUUGGGAUGCUGAGGCGGGUGGAUCACCUGAGGUCAGGAGUUUGCGACCAGCCUGGCCAACAUGAUGAAACCCUGUCUCUACUAAAAAUACAAAAAAAUUGGCUGGGUGUGGUGGCCCACACCUGUAAUCCCAGCACUUUGGGAGGUCGAGGCGGGUGGAUCACCUGAGGUCCGAAGUUCGAGGCCAGCCUGGCCAACAGGAUGAAACCCUGUCUCUAUUAAAAAUACAGAAAAUUGGCCGGGUGCGGUGGCUCACCCCUGUAAUCCCAGUACUUUGGGAGGCUGAGGCGGGUGGAGCACCUGAGGUCAGGAAUUCGAGAUCAGCCUGGCCAACAUGGUGAAACCCCAUCUCUACUGAAAAACACACACAAAAAAAUUAGCUGGGCAUGGUGGCACAUGCCUGUAAUCCCAGCUACUCAGGAGGCUGAGGCAGGAGAAUCAUUUGAACCUGGGAGGCGGAGCUUGCAGUGAGCCGAGAUUGCACCCCUGCACUCCAGCCUGGGCCACAGAGCAAGACUCUGUCUCAAGAAAAACAAAAAAAAAGAUAAAUGGACAAAAGACAUGAACAAACAGCUUUUAUAGGAUAGUAUGGCUAACAAACUUUUAGAAAAGUGUUUAGUCUCACUAGUAAGUAACAAAAUAUUGGGGCAGGGCACAGUGGCUCAUGCGUAUAAUCCUAGAACUUUGGAAGGCCAAAGCUGGUGGAUUGCUUGAGCCCAGGAGUUUGAGACCAGCCCAGGCAACAUUGGGAGACCCUGCCUCUACAAAUAUACAAAAAAAUUACUGGGCAUGGUGACACACACCUGUAGUCCCAGCUGUUCUGAAGGCUGAGGUGGGAGGAUCACUUGAGACCAGGAGAGGUCAAGGCUGCAGUGAUCUGUGAUCACACCACUGCACUCCAGCCUGGGCAACAGAGCAAAACCCUGCCUUUAAAAAAACAAAAAACAAAAAAGGCCGGGCUCGGUGGCUCAUGCCUAUAAUACUUUGGGAGGCCGAGGCAGGUGGAUCAAUUGAGGUCAGGUGUUCGAGACCAGCCAGGCCAACUUGGUGAAACCCCGUCUCUACUAAAAAUACAAAAAAAAAAAAAAAAAAUUAGCCAGAUGUGGUGGUGCACAUUUGUAAUCCCAGCUACUCAGGAGGCUGAGGCAGGAUAAUCGCUUGAACCUGGGAGGCAGAGGUUGCAGUGAGCCAAGAUCGCACCACUGCACUCCAGCCUGGGUGUCGAGUGAAACUCAUUCUCAAAAAAAAAAAAAAAAGGAGGUGGGGAGAGCUAUUUCAAGAAUAUUUUAAGUAGGCUGGGCACGGUAGCUCAUGCCUGUUAUCCUAACACUUUGGGAAGCCGACAUGGGCAGAUCACGAGGUCAAGAGAUUUGAGACCAUCCUGGCCAACAUGGUGAAACCCCAUCUCUACUAAAAAUACAAAAAAUUAUCUGGACAUGCUGGCGUGCGCCUGUAGUCUCAGCUACUUGGGAGGCUGAGGCAGGAGAAUCGCUUGAACCUGGGAGGCGGAGGUUGCAGUGAGCUGAUGUUGUGCUAGUGCACUCCAGCCUGGGCGACAGGGCUGAGACCUUGUCUCAAAAAAAAAAGGAGUAUCUUAAGUGUCUUUCAAAAUUACACUUUAGCACUUAUAAAUUUUAUAUAUAAUACUUUACUGAUAGCAUUGUAUAUUAGUCCAACUUUUUUGGCUACACUAUUUGUGAAGGAUUCCUUUUUUUCUUUAAGACAGCCACUGUAGGAAAUAUGCCAAGUACAGAUAGUGAGGAAAGAAAGGAAGAAAAAUGAUAAUUGUCUGCAAGUGGGCUUAUUUUUAACACUGCUGAAUUUCAUUUGUAAUUUUACUUUCAAGAAUAUACUCUGGUAGACUGAGGCGGGAGGAUCACUUGAGCCCAGGAGUUGGAGGCUUCAGUGAGCUGUGAUCACACCACUGCCCUCAGCCAAACCUGAGUGAUAAAGUGAGACCCUAUCUCUUAAAAAAAAAAAUCCCUUUGUUGUUGAGUUAUUUUAUGUCAUUUAUUGGUAAAUACCUAACAUUUUAGACCUAGUCAUUACCAGUUAACAUAGAAUUUAAUUGGAUGCAGUCUGUAUUUUUGAAAAAAAAAAUUUUUUUUGGAAUAACUUAAAUUCUAAAACUUUGGCCGGGCGUGAUGGCUCAUGCCUGUAAUCCCAGCACUUUGGGAGGCCGAGGCAGGCAGAUCACCUGAGGUCAGGCGUUCAAGACCAGCCUGACCAACAUGGAGAAACCCCGUCUCUACUAAAAAUACAAAAUUAGCCAGGCUUGGUGGUGCAUGCCUGUAAUACCAGCUACUCGGGAGGCUGAAGCAGGAGAACUGCUUGAACCUGGGAGGCAGAGGUUGCGGUGAGCCAAGAUCGCGCCAUUGCACUCCAGCCUGGGCAACAAGAGUGAAACUCCGUCUCAAAAAAAAAAGAAAAAUUCUAAAACUUUAAGUGAAAUUUAUUAUCCCUUCCCACUUAUUUUCUGUGGUUUUGUGUGUAUAGAGCAUCUUCCUUUGUUACCCAAGUACCUCGAAUGGGUUGGAAACUGGCGGUAGAAGGUUAGAGUAGCCAAUUGAUAUGUAAACCAAGUGUCAGAUCAGAUGAGAUGAAAGAGGUGGAGUUUAAAGCAAGUGAGAUAUGAUAAACAAUGAUGAAAGCAAAAAUAGGGCAGUUGAACCAGAGUCAGCCAGUUGGCAUAACUGCCAAUAAAUGAGGCAGUGUAGAAUAACUAAUAAUGAUUGGAAUCAAGGAAAAGAGAGCAUAGAGGAAUCAGCUAAAUUAGUAUGUUUUAUCCAUAGUUACAUGACUAACAAAUGAUUAAAAAGAAGUUAUUCUCUAGAUAAUUUUUUAAAUAAAAGUACUGUUAAUAUAUAAACUAAGUUAUUCAUUCACUGUUUUUCUUCACAGUAAGAAUGACAAAAAUCUGUGUUCUUUGUACUUAUCAAGUGACUCAAAUUUUGGCCACUUCACUGUCACUGAUGGCUUAUAGAAUGAUUCUAGCAGGACUCAAGUUAUUGAACUAUCAAAUGGGUUUUUAAUUGAUAUUGAAGUAAGUAAGUUUUGUAGCUUUUGGAGUUUUUAAAAACUACUUCAGUGAUUUUGAUUUAUAUUCUUUUUGAUAGUUCAGAAGUGUAUUGUUAAAAAACAUAAGCAUGGCCGGGCACAGUGGCUCACACCUGUAAUCCCAGCUCUUUGGGAGGCCAAGGCGGGUAAAUCACCUGAGGUUGGGAGUUUGAGACCAGCCUGACCAACAUGGAGAAACCCUGUCUCUACCAAAAAUACAAAAUUAGCCGGGCAUGAUGGAGCAUCCCUGUAAUCCUAGCUACUUGAGACGCUGAGGCAGGAAAAUUGCUUGAACCCGUGAGGCAGAGGUUGCGAUGAGCCGAGAUCGUGCCAUUGCACUCCAGCCUGGGCAAUAAGAGCAAAACUCCGUCUCAGAAAAAAAAAAAAAAAAAAAAAACGGCCAGGCGAGGUGGCUCACACCUGUAAUCCCAGCACUUUGGGAGGCUGAGGCGGGCAGAUCACCUGAAGUCAGGAGUUCAAGACCAGCCUGACCAACAUGGAGAAACUUCAUCUCUACUAAAAAUACAAAAUUAGCCGGGCGUGGUGGCACAUGCCUUUAAUCCCAGCUACUGGGGAGGCUGAAACAGGAGAAUCGCUUGAACCCAGUAGGGGAAGGUUGUGGUGAGCCAAGAUUGCACCAUUGCACUCCAGCCUGGGCAAGAAGAGUGAAACUCUAUCCAAAAAAAAAAAAAAACCAUACGUACAUAACUUUUUUUCUUUUUCUUUUCUUUCUUUCUUUUCUUUUCUUUUUUUUUUUUGAGGCACAGUCUUGCUUUGUUGACCAAGCUGGAGUGCAUUGGCAUGAUCACAGCUUACUGUAGCCUCCACCUCCUGGGCUCCAGCGAUCUCACCUCAGCCUCUAGAAUAGCUGGGACUACAUAUGCAUGCCACCAUGCCCAGCUGUUUUUUUGUUUGCUUGUUUUUGGUUUUGUUUUUUUGAGACAGGGUCUCCCUGCGUCGCCCAGUCUUGUCUCAAACUCCUAGGCUCAAGCGAUCCUCCCACCUGGGCCUCCCAAAGUGUUGAGAUUGCAGGUGUGAGCCACGGCACCUGGUCCAUAAAACAUUUUUUUAUGAACUAAAGAGCUCUCUCAAACUUGUGCUAACAAAAUUUAAGGCAAUAUUAAUUCUGUGCAUGUGUUUGGGAAAAUUAAAAAAACUUACAUAGUGCUUAUUUGGCCCACAAAAGUACAGUUCCAUUUUUUAUAUAAAUAGAUUCUACCUAACUUAUAACCCCUAUGUCAAAAUUUGUUUAUCUUAAAAUAGUUUGUAUAAAAAGUCUUUACUGCUUUAUUAUGAAAUAAUAAUGUUUAUUGUAGAAAAAUCUAGGAAAACACAAAAAUGUCAAACUCAGUUAACAGUCAUAGUUUCACUAUUUGAAGUUAACCACUGUUAAGAUUCUUUUUUUUUUUUUUUUUUUUUUGUUUUGAGACUGAGUCCCGCUGUCUAUUGCCCAGGCUGGAGUGCCAUGGCACCAUCUCGGCUCACUGCAACCUCUGCUUCCCAGGUUCAAGUGAUCCUCCCGCCUCAGCCUCCCAAGUAGCUGGGAUUGCAAACAUGUGCCACCACACCUGGCUAAUUUUUGUGUUUUUAGUACAGAUGGGGUUUCACCAUGUUGGCCAGGCUGGCCUCGAACUCCUCAACCUCAAGUAGUCUGCCCACCUUGACCUCCCAAAGUGCUGGGAUUACAGGCAUGGGGCACCAUGCCCAGCCCCACUGUUAAGAUUCUAAUGUAGGCCGGGCACAGUGACUCAUGCCUAUAACUCAAGCACUUUGGGAGUUCAAGGCGGCCAGAUUGCUUGAGCUUUUAGAAGUUUGAGACCAGCCUGGGCAACGUGGCAAAAGCUUGUUUCUAUAAAAAAAUAUAAAAACUUAGCCAGCCUUGGUGGCACCACCUGCAGUCCCAACUAUUCAGGAGGCUGAGGCGAGAGGAUGGCUUGAGCUCAGGAAGUCAAGGCUACAGUGAGCUGUGGUAGUGCCACUGCACUCCCUCAUGGUUGACAGAGCAAGACCCUGUCUCAAAAGAUUCUAAUAUAGAUACUCUUUUUAUGCAUAUGUAAUUUAUAUAUAUUAUACAAAAUAUUAUUUGCAUUUAACAUAUUCUGAACCAAUAGUCUUUUCUACAAGCAGAACAUUAGUAUUCUUGUCACUCUGAAUGUAGGCACAGAUUUUUGUCAUUCUUUAUCUUUUUUGUGUGUGUGUGACAGAGUCUCACUGUCACCAGGCUGGAAUGCAGUGGCGUGAUCUCGGCUCACUGCAACCUCUGCCUCCCAGGUUCAAGCGAUUCUCUUGCCUCAGCCUUUUGAGUAACUGGGGUUACAGGCGCGUGCCAUCACACCCAGCUCAUUUUUGUAUUUUUAGUAGAGAUGGGGUUUUACCGUGUUGGUCAGGCUGGUCCUGAACUCUUGACCUUGUGAUCUGCCCAACUCAGCCUCCCAGAGUGCUGGGAUUACAAGCAUGAGCCACCGCGCUCGGUCCCUUUCUUUUUAUUUAUUUAUUUAUUUUGAGAUGGAGUCUCGCUGUGUCACCCAGGCUGGAGUGUGGUGGCACGAUCUUGGCUCACUGCAACCCCUGCCUCCCAGGUUCAAGCAAUUCUCCUGCCUCAGCCUCCUGAGUAGCUGAGACUACGGGUAUGUGCCACUACACUCAGCUAAUUUUUGUAUUUUUUUUUAGUAGAGACAGGGUUUCACCAUGUUGGCCAGGCUGGUCUUGAACUCCUAACCUCAGGUGAUUCACACCCCUUGGCCUCCUGAAGUGCUGGGAUUACAGGCAUGAGCCACUGUGCCCGGCCAUUUUUUUGUGUUUUUAGUGGAGACAGGUUUUCACCAUGUUGGCCAGUAGUGUAUUUAGUUAUUUAAGGAGGGCUCAAUCAACAGGUUUAAAUGGUGUGCUAUUCAUAAUUAUUGCAAAAAUAGGCCGGGCCUGUAAUUCCAGCACUUUGGGAGGCCAAGGCAGGUGAAUCACUUGAGGCCAGGAGUUUGAGAUCAGCCUGGCCAACGUGGUGAAACUCCAUCUCUACUAAAAAUACCAAAAGUAGCGGGCGUGGUGACAGGUGCCUCUAAUCCCAGCUACUCGGGAGGCUGAGGCAGGAGAAUCGCUUGAACCCAAGAGUCGGAGGUUGCAGUGAGCCGAGAUCGCGCCAUUGCACUCCAGUGUGGGUGACGAGCGAAAAUCCGUCUCAACCAAGAAAAAAGAAAAAAAGAAAAAGAAAACUUAACUGGCCUUUGGGGCACAUGCCUGUAAUCCCAGCUUCUUGGGAGGCUGAGGCAUGAGAAAAAAAAUAAACCUGGGAGGUGGAGGUUGCAGUGAGUUGAGAUUGUGCCACUGCACUCCAGCUUAGGCAAUAAAACAAGACUGUCUCAAAAAAAAAAAAAAAAAAAACUUAUUGAGAGAAUAAUAUACCACUAAUAUUUAAAGAAAUUUUUGGCUGGUGCCGUGGCUCACACCUGUAAUCCCAGCACUUUGGGAGUCCAAAGUGGGCGUAUAACUUGAGGUCAGGAGUUCAAGAACAGCCUGGCCAACAUGGGGAAACCGCAUCUCUACUAAAAAUACAAAAAUUAGUGGGUGUGGAGGCGGGCGAAUGUAAUCCCAGCUAGUUGAGAGGCUGAGGCAGGAGAAUGUCUGGGAGGUGGAGGUUGCAGUGUGCCGAGAUCGCACCACUGUACUCCAGCCUAGGUGACAGAGUGAGACUCCAUAGGUCUCAGCCAGACUCUGGAGGUCUCAGCCCAGGCUUGAGUGCAGUGGCAUGAUCUGGGCUCACUACAACCUCCAUCUCCCCAGUUCAAGCGAUUCUCCUGCCUCAGCCUCCCGAGUAGCUGCGACUACAGGCGAGUGCCUCCAUGCCCAGCUAAUUUUUUGUAUUUUUAGUAGAGACGGGGUUUCACCAUGUUAGCCAGGAUGGUCUUGAUCUCCUGACCUUGUGAUCUGUCCACCGCGGCUUCCCAAAGUGCUGGGAUUACAGGUGUGAGCCACAGCGCCCGGCCAAAAAAAGGAAUUUUUAAGAGGAAAAAGAAUGCUACCAACCUAAACACAUUUCUGUGACUGUUUAUAUUUUUCCCUGUUCCACAUACAUACAUUUUUACAUAGUACGUUCAUUGCAGCAUGAGUUACUUUUCACUUAAUAAAUUUUAAACAUUUUCCAGCUGGGUGUGGUGGCUCAUGCCUGUAAUCCCAACACUUGGAGAGGCCAAGUCAGGCUUAUUGGGUGAGUCCAGGUGUUUGAGACUAGCCUAGGCAACAUGGCGAAACUGCAUCUCUACAAAAAAUACAAAAAUUAGCCAGGUGUGCUGGCGCACACCUGUAGUCCCAACUACUCAGGAGGCUGAGGUGGGAGGAUUGCUUGAGCCCAGGAGGUAGAGGUUGCAGUGAGCCAUGAUCAUGCCACUGCACUCCAGCCUAGGUGACAAAGCACAACCCUCAAAUAAAUAAAUAAAUACAUGUUAAACAUAUACCUUUAUUACUUCAUUUUUGUAAGAGCUUCAGGGAAUAGGCUUUUUUAAAGGGAAUAGACUUAUAGAUCAAUUUUAAUAUUUGACUUAUAGAAUUUUAUGACACUAAAUGGAUAAUUGUAAAGUUUGAGUUGGGACCCAUUUUUUAAGACAUUCAGGCUAUAAACAAGGUAAUAAAUCACACUCUUCCAGUUCUACUCCCAAUUUAAUUGGUUUACAGUUCGGUGGCUGUCUUUUUUUUUUUUUUUUUUUUUUUUUGAGACCGAGUCUCCCUCUGUCACCAGGCUGGAGUGCAGUGGUGCAAUCUCAGCUCACUGCAACCUCCCCCUCUCAGGUUCAAGUAAUUCUCCUGCCUCAGCCUGCCGAGUAGCUGGGACUACAGUCGCACGCCAACCACCCCCAGCUAAUUUUUUUAUUUUUAGUAGAGACAGGAUUUCACCAUGUUUGCCAGGAUGGUCUCGAUCUCUUGUGCUCAUAAUCUACCUACCUCGGCCUCCCAAAGUGCUCGGAUUACAGACGUGAGCCACUGCGCCCGGCCCGUUGGCUUGCUUUCUAGAUACUGGGAAUAGAUCUUGUUAUAGUAUGUGAUAAAUAGAUCUUGUUAUAGUAUGUGAUAAAAUGCCAUGAUCAAAUAAAUUACUUAUAUCCUGUUUGGUGAUUUUUAGAAAAACAUAUUUAUCUACAUCUAAAAUACUUAUUUUAAUUUUAAACACUUGAUGGUAUGAAAUGAAAUUUUGUUACUUUACCAUUGUAACUAUGUCAUAAAGUCAUAAAGUACCUGUCCCCAAAAAGGCAACCAGUAAAUAUUUUUGAGUAAAUGAAUGAAAUCUUUAUUGCCGGUGUUCUGUGCACAUAGAAUAAAGGAAAUUAUUAAUGUUACUUAAUAGUUUAAAAAAAUUCAGAAGCCAAGCUAUCCAUAAAGCUACUUUGUGAUGUGCUGAAUACUCCAUUAAUAGAAGUGUUUAAGAGGAUGUUGUAUGCCUGCCUUCCACUCAUGCCUGUGUUAGAUGUGAACAUAGAUUUAUAAUAUAGUACUAUACAAAAUACAACUAAAAUAGUUGGUAA